ACAAGAGAACAACUUGCUCCUUCCACAGGAAGCUGCACCUGACAGAAGCUCCAGGAUGCUUGUUCUCUUUCUCCUGGGCACAGUCUUUCUGCUCUGCCCAUAUUGGGGUGAACUUCAUGACCCUAUAAAAGCGACUGAAAUAAUGUGUUAUGAAUGUAAAAAAUAUCAUCUUGGGUUAUGCUAUGGUGUCAUGACAUCCUGCUCCCUGAAGCAUAAACAGUCCUGUGCAGUUGAGAACUUUUACAUCCUUACAAGGAAAGGGCAGAGCAUGUAUCAUUAUUCAAAACUGUCGUGUAUGACCAGCUGUGAGGACAUCAACUUCCUGGGGUUCACGAAGAGGGUAGAGCUCAUCUGUUGUGAUCAUAGUAACUACUGCAACCUCCCUGAGGGAGUUUAGUUCUACGUCUCUCCUGGAUUUUGGGUUCUUUUUCAACCACUACGCUCUUUUUCUCUUCCCUGAACCUGAAUUUUGCUCUCCUCUUCUAUGCAUUGGUAGAGAGUGAGAAAGCCAGCUCAUAGUGAAAAGACAAGCAGGCAUAAGGAGACGCAGUGUGGACAGCGGAGCCUAUUGAUGAUGGAGCACUAGACUCACUCUUUGCACAUCCCUGUCGCUAACAGGUGGGAGGGGUUUUGCUCUCCUUACGUGAUACUGCCAUGAAUAAGCUCAGACUUGGUCAUUUAUUAUCUCCUGUAUGAAAAUGUGAACACUUGGGCCAUAAUAAUCUCCAAUUUGUACUGAGAAUUCUGUGACUAUCCUCUAUCCUCAUCUACACACACACUCCUCUCCGUUGGAAUUCUCUUUGGAUUAGCCCUGACACUUUCUGGCACUGUCCUUUUCUGCCCGUGGGUUCUGGAGAGGGCUAACCCCAGCUUCCCAGUGUGUUGGCAGCAUGGGCCAAGUCUUUCUCUGAUAGAGCUCUUGGGGGAACCUCAGGGCAGAAAAAAAAAAACUGAACAGACAUAGGGAUGAGCAUCAAAGAAAACUUCAGGGGGCAUUUCAACUGGUAAAAACUAAGAUCUGAGAAAUAACUUGCUGUGGGUGGAAUUGGCUUGAAUUAUCAUUGCCCUGGCUGGCCAGGCAGCCUUGGGCACAUGGUUGAACUAGGUGAUUGGAUUGGGAACAGAGUGUUUUUUUAAGGAUGGCUAGUCAGGUUCUUCUCAUGGGACUGAGCAAACAAAAUGCUGAUAAUGUGGCAGGUGGUGUAGUAGUUGAAGAUAAUAGGAUGUAAAUAGAUACCAUGAGGUAGUGUUCAAGUAACAGAGUGCCCUGUGUAAGAGGAAGUUAUGAGUUUGCAGAAAGUGUGAGAAAGGUAGCAUAUAUGGGUAACAGUGGUGGGAAGAGAAGAAGGAAGACACAGAAACAGAUAGGAAGAGAAACUGAGUAGCAUUGAUGUUGGAGCACACCUGUGGCCAAGGUGGCACAUUUUCCUUGGAUACACACUAACCCUGGUGUUUCUGUCCUUAUAAGGCUGACUGCACCCUAGAUGACGGGUUGAUGGGUGCAGCAAACCACCAUGGCACAUGUAUACCUAUGUAACAAACCUGCAUGCUGCACUUUCUUUCAUGUAUCCCAGAACUUAAAGUAAAAUAAAAAAAUAAAUAAAUAAAUAAAGGCCAGAAAAAUUGGCCAAAAAAUCUGAAUAGAAAAAGAUAUACAGAUAGUAAA